CCCUUUCGCUGCGGCCGCCCGCGAGGAGCCUGGCUGAGGCAGCCGCGCAGGUCGCAGGGCCAGCGUCCGCGAGGACGGCCCGGCUGGGCGGCCCCGAGCUCUGUGGCGCUGUGGAGGAGCGGGAGCGCGGCCGAGGAAGCGGGGCGCCGAGGGGGUCGGCGGCCUUCGGGAAAUUUCCGCCGACCCUUCGCUCCCGGCUCUAAAAGUUCCUGAUUUCCUAUUUCCUUUUAAAUCCCGAGUGGCUGUUAGCUCUUCGCCUGCACUUUUUCUUCCCCAGGAGAUAAGGGGGAGUGUGAGGAACGGAGCGAAUAAUAUAAAAAAGGAUUUCCUCCCGGAAGAGAGCGGCAGUUCGGAGAGAUUUUUCUUAAGGAAGCAGAAGCGGCGUUUGCGGCCGCUGCAGGCGCCGGGCCCUGCCGGCCACACUAUGCGCGAGCCGGCCCCGGGCUGCUGAGGCGCGGGGACGCGGAAGCGGAGGCCGAGCGCGCCGGGCUCCCGCGCUCGCGAGCGAGUUUUGUCCGCCCGGCGGCGGUGGCGGGGGGAUGGAGCCCGCGACCGCGCCCCGGCCCGACAUGGCGCCGGAGCUGACCCCGGAGGAGGAGCAGGCUACCAAGCAGUUUCUCGAAGAGAUUAACAAGUGGACAGUUCAGUACAAUGUUUCCCCGCUGUCUUGGAAUGUGGCUGUCAAGUUCCUCAUGGCAAGGAAGUUUGAUGUGCUCCGUGCCAUAGAAUUGUUCCACUCCUACAGAGAAACUCGAAGGAAGGAAGGCAUUGUAAAGCUGAAACCUCAUGAGGAACCUCUUCGUUCUGAGAUCCUCAGUGGAAAAUUCACCAUCUUAAAUGUUCGGGACCCAACAGGAGCCUCCAUUGCCCUCUUUACUGCCAGGUUGCAUCAUCCCCACAAGUCAGUCCAACAUGUGGUACUUCAGGCUCUGUUUUACUUGCUAGACAGAGCUGUGGAUAGCUUUGAAACUCAGAGGAAUGGACUGGUGUUUAUCUAUGACAUGUGUGGUUCUAAUUAUGCCAACUUUGAGCUGGAUCUUGGCAAGAAAGUCCUAAACCUGCUGAAGGGAGCAUUUCCAGCUCGUUUGAAGAAGGUGCUGAUUGUGGGGGCACCCAUAUGGUUCCGAGUGCCCUAUUCCAUCAUCAGUCUCCUCCUGAAGGACAAAGUCCGGGAGAGGAUUCAAAUAUUAAAGACAUCUGAGGUCACGCAGCAUCUGCCCAGGGAGUGUCUUCCAGAAAACCUGGGUGGGUACGUCAAAAUUGAUCUCGCCACUUGGAAUUUCCAGUUCCUACCCCAGGUGAACGGCCACCCAGAUCCCUUCGAUGAGAUCAUCCUGUUCUCCCUCCCUCCUGCCUUAGACUGGGACUCAGUACAUGUUCCAGGUCCCCAUGCUAUGACCAUCCAAGAGUUGGUGGACUAUGUUAAUGCCAGGCAAAAGCAAGGAAUCUAUGAGGAAUAUGAAGACAUUCGUCGUGAGAACCCUGUUGGCACUUUCCACUGUUCCAUGUCUCCAGGAAACCUAGAGAAAAACCGUUAUGGGGAUGUACCCUGCCUGGACCAAACUAGAGUGAAGCUAACAAAGCGAAGUGGCCAUACUCAGACAGAUUACAUCAAUGCCAGUUUCAUGGAUGGCUACAAGCAGAAGAAUGCUUACAUUGGCACACAAGGUCCUUUGGAGAAUACCUAUCGUGAUUUCUGGCUCAUGGUAUGGGAGCAAAAAGUCUUGGUGAUUGUCAUGACCACCCGCUUUGAGGAAGGCGGCAGGAGAAAGUGUGGCCAGUACUGGCCUUUAGAAAAAGACUCUCGGAUCCGAUUUGGCUUCCUCACAGUGACCAAUCUAGGCGUGGAGAACAUGAAUCAUUAUAAGAAAACAACGCUAGAAAUUCACAACACAGAGGAACGGCAGAAACGCCAGGUGACCCACUUCCAGUUCUUGAGCUGGCCAGACUAUGGUGUCCCUUCCUCAGCAGCUUCCCUCAUUGACUUCUUGAGAGUGGUCAGAAACCAGCAGAGUCUGGCUGUGAGCAACAUGGGAGCACGCUCCAAAGGGCAGUGCCCUGAGCCACCCAUUGUGGUCCAUUGCAGUGCAGGCAUUGGCAGGACAGGUACCUUCUGCUCACUGGACAUCUGCCUGGCACAGCUGGAGGAGCUUGGCACCCUUAAUGUGUUCCAGACGGUGUCACGCAUGAGGACCCAGAGGGCCUUCAGCAUCCAGACCCCUGAGCAGUACUAUUUUUGCUACAAGGCCAUCCUGGAGUUCGCAGAGAAGGAGGGCAUGGUAUCCUCUGGCCAAAACCUGCUGGCCGUGGAGAGUCAGUAACUCUCCUACGAACCUCCUACCUGUUGGCCAGCCUUCCUUAAACUACCCUGGACACCGCUGAGCCUAUAGGUUGCCAUCAGUUACGCUGAAGCCAUGGAUCAACUUCUUUCUUGUGUCUCCCAGCACACGUGUGCACGCAAGGCAGCCUUUCCCUUUGGCUAGAUAAAUGUGGUGAAAUUGCCACUAGAAAGGGCCAGUAGCAAUGUGUUCUUAAUUCCUAGCAUCUGCUAUCAAACUGUGCCUUAUUAAAACCAAAUUGUGGCUAUUGAUUUUUGCUAGGGUCCCCGAGGUAAGUGGGGAAGGAACCUCCCUCCUCCUUUCUCCCGCCAUUCUUUUUCUGAGGUCUCCUGUCUCCCACUCCUUCCCUUUCCUAGGAUUUUAUGGGGAGGUUUGAUGAGCAUUUGCCUUUCUCCCCAGAGAGCUUGACCAAGUUACAUAUUCUAGAGAUCGUCCUGAGUGCCAAGCACGUUUAUAAGUAGGGCGUGUAUUCCAGUCCUUUCUGUCAUUCUGUGUGUGUGUGUGUGUGCACUUAUGUGUAUGGGUCCAUAUGUACGUGUGUAUAUAAUAUAUAUUGUAUGUGAUAAUAUGAUCGUAUUCUAUAAAUACAUAUACACACGAUACUCCUUUCCAGAAGUUCCUGGGGCUCCGUGUUGCAGUUCAGGACUCCUUGCUUCUUGGACCCUACUAUUUAUCCUGGACUAGCUUGGGUUGGUGAUCAUGUCUCCUCUUGUCAGGCUACAGAGUGGUGGAAGAGGACACACACACAUCUCCUCCAUGUUCCUGCCACAGGGCCCCUUCCUUAAGUAAUGACUUAUCUCCUUCCAGUUGCCACCUGUUGGAGCCAAGAAUGUAUUAGUUUGUGGUGACACUGGGUUAGCUCAGCAUGGAUUUCCCUUAUCCGAUGAUUUUUCUACAUUUACUUGGCCAAUUUGGGGAACAGACCUCCACUGUGAUUCCAUACUCUCUCUUUGCUUUCACUAUCCCAGGGAUGGGAGGCGGAGGGUAGAGAUGAACUCACUGAGCAGCCAGAGCCAAAUGCAAUCGGUACGAAUCUUAGAAGGAAGGAGGGGGAGCCCAGGUAUGAGAAAGAAAAAACCACUAAGAAAAUACCUCCCUGGGAGGAUGAGCUGGGGCCCUUUUUCUUUUGCUGGAUGGUUCCUUUAUGCAGCUUGGCCCUGUCUACCGAGAUGCCCAUCUCUUCCUGCCUGCUAGCCUGCUAGACCCUCAAACUGGGUGGGUUCUGUGUCAAUAAAAAGCUUCACCCCCUGGCUGAGUGAGGUGGUCCCCUGCAAUCACUGUUUGUCCCCUACCCACCCAACCUGUCCCUGCCUGCUCCCAGCCCACUCAUCCUUAUGUGCUAGGGAUAAAUCAAGAGUCCUCAGCACUCCACAUUCCCAAAAAAUCCCAGGAACUCCUAAACCUUCCCCUGUGACAGAAGAUGAGGUUGGCAGCUGAUCAGACCUCAAUAAUUUUAUACUGUAAUAAGCUCUUUGAAUGUGUAUAUUAUUAUUUUUUACAAUCAUUUCAUUUUGUAUUUAAUAUCAAUGGACUGAGUCUGAUUCAGAAAAUAAUUGUAAUGUUCAUAUUCAAUAUCUUACAGUGAUACAGUUUUGUAUUUACAUAUAAAUAUACCGACAUGAUCAAAACCCUUUUAGCUUCAUCAAUUUAGCAGCCUGGGACAUGAGGGAGGGGGUCCAGGAGCUGGUCUGGGAGGGAUGAGGGAGGCAGGGAGGGACCCAAGCCUUCAGUAUCUGAGACUUUGAGUUCUGACACUAUGAGUUCACCUUGUCUGUAGGCCAUGGCCCUAUCUCUGGACAGAGGGACCAGCACCAGUUCAGUGCUUGAGAUGUGCUAAGCACUAUGCUAGGUGCUUUUCCCCCACCCUGCCUCAUUCAAACCUCACAACAAUUCAGUGAGAUAUUAUCUUCUCUCCCUUCUCCUGUGCACCCCUUUCUCAUUUCUAUAUAGAUGAGGAAGGUGAGGUCCAGAGGGUUACAGUGAUUUGCUCUAAAACGAGCUCAAGUUGGUCUGCUUACAAAGCCUGUGGUCUCUUCACUGCAUGGAAGAUGGAGAUCUUGUGUUUGGAGAACAGAGGUUUGUUUAGCUCUCCUUUCAGAGUAAAAAAAGUUCUUAAAUUCCAGGUUGUUGUUCUUGUGCCCAUGCUUCAUGUAGUAGACGCGAAGGGUGACAGGGUUGGUGACUGACUGUCCUAGCUAGGACCUCCUGAUGUAGGGUCCUCAUGUCUGCAGCGUACCAAAGGGGUUAUCAUUCUCCCCAGGAGACUCCAUAUCUAUGGGUACAUGGUCUUUGUGAGAAGAUCUUGAGUCAUUUGCAUUUAUCUCUUAGAAAGAAAGGAACCAGAAGCUUUGUACAUGGAAGACCACUCCCCAUAUCAUACCUGUUGGCUGUUGAUGGCCUGCCCAGUUGGGGCAGUUGUGGCUGGGAAAUAUUGGGGUGUUCUUAAUAAUAGUCAUAGCAGCCAAUUUACUGGAUGCUCACUCUAUUCCAGGCACUGUUCAGAGUAAUUUCUAGGUAUCAUCUCAUUCACCCUCAACAACCUUUUGAGGUAGGUAUUGACAGAAGAAAAAAAUUGAGAGACAGGAAUGUUAAUUUGCUACAGCCAGGAUCCCAGACCAUCUGACUCCAAAGUAUCUUCUUUCACCUCUUACACUAGACUUCCUCUAAGGAUCCAUCUUCUGAUCUGCCAAUAAAUUUUUAUCGAGUUUCUUACCAUAAUCAGGAGCUCAAGUGUAGAGCAGAAGAUUAAUCUAGUUCCUUCUCCAGAUGAGCCUCCAUUCUCUUGGGAGUGCACAAACAUAAGAAGUGAACAGAGAUUCUUGGAAAUCUGAGAAACCAGAGAGGUCAGGGGUUUGGUGGAACAUGUAAGAAAUGGGAUUAAUGAUAAACGGCCUGGAGGAGGUAACUUUAAAUUGUCAUUUAUUUGAAGAGGCUGUAACCCGACUGCCCUGUGAAUUUAAGGUUAUGCAUGAGUUCCUCAUUGCAUAUCUGAAGACUGGUGAGGUUAUCUAUCACUUCAGCUCCAUAAAAUGCUGAUUUCUGGGCCCAUCCAGUAGGUUGUUAGUGAGUGACAGGAUUAUCCAGGUUUGGGAACCAUAGAUUUAGUUCAUGUUUCUGACCCUAUAGAGAGUUAACAAAUUGAUGUCUCCUAAAUUUUCAGUAAAACUCAGAGGAACUCCUCCCACUGCCAUUGUUUGUAGCUUUUACCAGCGUGAACCUACCUGUGUUAGGUGUUAAAGGAGGAGGUAAAGGAAAGGGAAGGCAGAGACGCAACCCAGAAUCUGUUUGGCAAGUCAGGGUUCUCAUACAGGAGACUUAGUGAACAAAGCAAGAGAAAAUGCUCAGGGUCCAAGUGCAGUGGCUUUAUGCCUGUAAUCCCAGUACUUUGGAAGGCCGAGGUGGGCAGAUCACCUGAGGUCAGGAGUUUGAGACCAGCCUGACCAAUAUGAUGAAACCCCAUCUCUACUAAAAAUAUAAAAAUUACCCGGGUGUGGUGGUAUGUGCUUGUAAUCCCAGCUACUCGGGAGGCUGAAAUGGGAGAAUCACUUGAAUCUGGGAGGCAGAGGUUGCAAUGAGCCGAGAUCGCGCCAUUGCACUCUAGCCUGGGCAACAAGAGUAAAACUCCAUCUCAAAAAAAAUAAAUAAAUAAAAAAGAAAGACAGUGUUCAGGAAAGAAGAAAACACUGAGCUAAAGCAGGCUUCUGCUUCUGAUUUGAUGGCUGUUUGUUUCACCUUUCUCUAACAUUCCCAUGCUAUAUAAUUUUUCAAACAUGAGAUAAUCCCUGUGUCCUUUUUCCCAUUGCUCCCUUCAUCUUGCCCAUCCUCAUUGGCUAGGAUGGGACUCCUGAGACGAAGGGUGCCCCAGCAUCCUCAGCCUCGGAGGCCCACCCUUAUCAGUCUUCAUGUGACAGUAUGCAGGUAAAUGACAGAGUAGGACUUGUUCUUGGGAGAAUGGACUAUUUAGCAUCAUAGCCCUAGGGAAAUUUGGUUCCUUCCCUGAAAGGAAUGCUUCCUGUCUCUUGGGACAGACAGACACACAUACAAAAACUUUUAUAAAUCAGAGACCUAGAGGGAAUUGGGCCAAGAGGCAUUGGCCAAGUAGAAAAGCUUCUCUAGAGUGACCCAGCUCUUUUGUGGUUUUGAGGUCUUACCACUGAACCAAACCCAAGUCCUAGGUUCCCUCUGUAAAAGAAGGGGCUACACUAGAUGAUCCUACCAUGGGUCCUCUGACUGUCAGGGUCCAGUUCUUUGUUAGACAGUGCAAACACCCAUAGAGGAGCUAUUAGGCCUUUACUUGGGUUGAGUUGGCUCCCACUAGCACUCCCCACUUUUCAUUUUUUUUACUUUCAGAGACAGAGUCUCACUCUGUUGCCUAGGUUAGAGGGGAGUGGCAUGAUCAUGGCUCACUGCAGUCUCAACAACUGGGCUCAAGCAGGAACCCAGCUUUUUUUUUUUUUCUCUCUCUCUCUCUAGAGACAGGAUCUCACUAUGUUGCCCAGGCUGGUCUCGAACUCCAGCCUCAAGCAAUCCUCCUGCCUCGGCCUCCCAAAGUGAGAGGAUUACAGGCAUGGGCCACCACACCCAGCCUCUCCAGUUUUAGUGUGUUUUCAGAGUCUCUUCUUUCAAGCUGCUGCUACUUCCCUAGCUUCCCUCAGUUCUCUUCCCCCUUGGCCUUCCAAUUGGAGGAAAAGCAGGUCAGGUCUCUGUCAUCUCCAAGACCAGCCUAUAGGCCUUUAAAGUUUCCCUGUUUCUUAAUGUGGGGUCUACAGGGUUUCUCAGAGGCAAAGCAUGAACAGACCAAGGGUCCUAUAGCUCCCAACCUAGUCCUUAGAUUUCUCUCUGGCCUUGGUUACUCCCACAAACCACUGUGAGCCUACCAAGGGCAGGAAUGGAAAUGCCCAUCAGCCUGGGAACCAUCUUUUUCUCUUAGGAGGUAUCCGCCCUAUAGUUACCUUUACACAACACUUGUGAAUAUCAAGUGUUCUAGACUGCACUGUUCAUAAUUGACUACAGAGAAGACUAGGAUCUUCUCCACAAAUAGAAAUAUAUCACUUUUACUUGGAGAUGUUUUCUUGGGGGAAAAAAAAUCUAGCACCUUGAAACCUGUUACAAUGUUUAAAUCUCCCUUCUUUACCUUGGCUGUCAUAAAAUCCUCCUGUUUGAGCUAAAUGUGGCCUGCUGAAGUCUUAAAUGCCCAUAUUUUUCAGGCUAAGGCCAUGGUGGACAUAGCUAACUCCACUAGAAUCCUAGCUGGGGGUGUUGGAAAAAACGGUACAGUGCCCCUCUCAGACUCCAGGCUCACGUCCGUCUCCCCUCCCCGCACAUUAUAAUCUACUACUUCUCUAAUGCUGCUGCGUAGUUUGUCUUAAAGCCUCAAGACUGGCCAGAUGUGCACCUGAGUAAAGGUCAGCCAUUUCAUCUGGGGGCUCUUUCUUGACUUUUAAUGAAUUUUCUUCUGUGAAAAAAUGUAUUUUUAAUAAAAAAUUUUCUGUGGCCAGCA